CUGUUGUCAUUGUUGUUCCUACCCUGUCUUCCUGGGAGCAAUGGUAGCCUCUUAAAUUUACAAACAACCGAACCAAGGCAACAAGAUGUGAGGGCAGGGCCAGGCUAUGCAGUGGGUGUGGCAGAGACUCCACCCCCCUGGCUGAGUUUCUCUGAGAUAGAUAAAACCACCUGGGACACUUCUCCACUCACUAGCUGUGUGACUUUAGGCAAAUUACUUAACCUUUCUGUGUCUCAUUAGUCAGAUUAAUGGAAUGAAGAUAGUAAUAGUAGCAUUUUCUCUUAGGGGUGCUGUGAGGAUUUAAUGAGGUGAUACAUGUAAAGUGUUUACAGCCCGGGAGGUCAGGGGGAUGAGAUGAGCAUCCUGGUUGGACAGGGCCGUGGGCCUCAAACUACUGUAGUGGUGGCUCCAACAGGAGCCUCUCAGAGUAUUGCUCAUUGGAAGCACAAAGGCCAUUCACAGGGACACUGUCAUUCACCUUGAUAUGAGUGGGUCAGGGAAGGCAGUCUGAUUAGCAGACACCUGGAAGAAGUGUUUGAACUGCGGGGUUGUGGGGGCUGUGUGAGCCAUGCCAGAAUCUGAAGGAAAAAUGUGGACUGUACAAGGCAGAGGAGAAAGAAAGUGGGGAGAGCCCAAGAUGAGAGUGUGCUUUGCUAAUUCAAAGAAAAGCAAGAGGUCAGUAUGUAUGGCUAGGAGUAAAUGAAGACAGCAGUGAUAUGGUUCAGAGGGAGACUGGACCUGCAGGGCCUUGUAGUAUGGGUUUUGAUCAAGGAGAAAGGAAACUGGCACUUGCUGAGGACACAUCGUGUGCUAAGCUCUGGGCUGGGUCUAAUCUUUUUAAUAAUUCUGCAAGAGCAGCUGGUACAGAUGAGAAAGAGGAGCUUACAUUCUUGCGUAUAAUCAAUCAGGUGGCUCACACAUGGCAAAACCAGAAUUUAGACAAGGUCUUUUGGAUUUCAGAGCAUACUCCAGACCUGCUUCAAAUUUAGACAUUUGUUAAUUAUCUAGUAUUUGAAUAUACUUGUUUAUUUCUUUGCUUCAAGUCAACUGAGAUGAUACAGGAAAGCUAAAUUUCAACUCGCUAAUUUGCAUGAACACAAUUAAUGACUGUAAAAAAUCUUUUUGGAAGGAAGAUUGUACCAGAUAUGGUUUCAUUGCUUGAGCAAAUUAACACAUCCCCUGUUACCUGGUAUGCAUUAAUCUGGGUUCUUCAGAUAAAUAGAACCAAUAGGAGAUAGAUACGGAUACGGAUAUGGCUACAGAUAGAAAGAGAUUUAUUUAAGUAAUUAACCAACAUGGUUAUAGGGGCUCAGAUGUCCCAAGAUCUGCAUCUGGCAAGCUGGAGACCCAGGAGAGCUGAUCAUAUAGUUCCAGCCUAAGUCAGAAGGGCUGAGAACCAGGAGAGCUGAUGGUAUAAGUCUGGUUCAAGUCUGAAUCCAAAUGCAGGAGAGGACUCAUCUUCUAGCUUAAAGACACAGAAGCAAAGAGAGAAAAUCCCCCCCCUUUAAUUCACCUUUUGUUCUAUUCAGGCCUUCAAGGGAUCUGUUGAGGCCCAUCCAUAUUAAAGAGUGCCACCCACUUUACUCUUUCUACUGAUUUAAAUGUUAAUUUCUUCCACAGAUACCGUCACAGCAACAAACAGAAUAAUGUUUAACCAAAUAUCUGGGUACCCCAUGCUCCAGUCAAGUUGAUACAUAAAAUUAACCAUCACAAAUACCAUUUUUUAUGAAUGUAAGUACAAUUAAAGAAAAUGUCAAGUCGCAACAAGGAGGCUCCCACACUGCACGUGGCUUCUCUGGUCUUGCAGGGAGGCCUGAGCUUGCCUGCCCCAGAGCCCCAUUUUUCCUUGCACUGAUCAGCUUCUCUAGAUUCCUGAGACUUCUUUUGCCUAUACAAGUUCUCUCCAUUUUCAAAAGCUCUGCCUCAUAGGACAACUAAACAGGCAGCAUUCUUUAAGAUAAUCUUGAUAAGGGAUUUUCAAAAUGUGCUAUGUCAUGGCUGCAUGGAAAAUGGUCAUAUUUGUACAGCACACAGAAGAAAUGGAUGAAGCUGCUUGUAGCCACAGGGUAGUGGCCUGGUGGGGGAGGAUGAACUCUAGACAUCUUGAUUCUACCAACUGUCUCCUUAGACCACAAGUGUACCUUUGCUACAUGGUUGGAAAAAUCUGAUUGAAAUCAAGCCAUCCAUCUUAUAGGUGGGAAUACUGAGGCCCAGAGAGGGAAAGACUAGAGCUAGAGCCACCUCCUUUUCUCCUGGGACCUGCCUGUGCAGUUCUGGUCAUACUGCAUUGCCUGUCUGAUCCUUUUCUGCCUCCUCAUUUCUGAAUUAUUCAUUGGGCAUUUGUCACAAACUGUCAGGGACAGCUGACUUGUGUGGGUGUGUGCGUGUAUAAGCACAUAUGAUCUUUUCCCAAUUAGAUAAUAAAUCAUCUGGGGACAGGGUCUUUUUCGUGUUCUCUUUCUUUUCUUAUACCCUCCAAAUUACCAGGCAUAUCAGGUCAUACUUUUCUAUGUAUUAAAGUAUAAAUGAAUAAUCAUCCAUCAUUAGCCUUUAAAAUAAACUGUAGCAUCCUCCUACUUCAAAUGUCUUUUCUUCCAGAAAGUAUUUGCUGAUACCUAGCUGUCAAUGAUCUCUGGUUUGUCUCACCUUCCAAAGCAUUUUCUUUGUGACAUCGUAGAGCUUUUACUGCUUUCCACCUUAUAUUAGAGUCAUAGGUAGAAAUAUCCCAUCUCCUUUUCCAAUGACGUGAUCACCUUGAAGGUAGAAUACAUGUGGCUCGUGUAAUACAGUGGUGUUUACUUCACAGGCAUUCAAUUCUAACUCCGCAUUUUAAAAUGUCUAUUACAUAUCAGAUACUGCACUAGCCGUGUCAUUGCAGGAGCUCAUUUAAACUCCACAGCGGCUAUAUAAGGUGCAUAUCCGCUUCGUUUUUAUUAUAUAAGGAAGCUGAUGCUCAAAGAGGGGAGGUACCUAGUUCCAGACUGAGUUGAAGCCAAACUUCUGGUUCCAAAUGCCAUACCUUUGUUUUAGCCCAGGAUCGUUGCCUGCUUAUCUUAGCAAAUGUUUGUGGAAUAAAUAUGCAAGCCAAGAAUAGGUGAGUUAAUUCAUUUGAAGGCUAGCAAAUGCUGAACAUAAGUCAUUUGUGGCUUUUGGAAAUUGUUGUGAAAAUACCUUUAUACUGUAAAAAAUGAAAAGAACGUUGAUUCUCAUGGAUCACUUCUGCUCGCCUAUGGAUUGUCCCUGAAACAUCUGCAAGUUCAAUUGAAAUAUGACUUUCAGAUGAAAGAAUGCUAUCACUGUCCCAAGGCUUUCUUUCCUGAUUUGUACCAACAUCAAAGUAGAAGUUUAUACUUUUUCAUUUUAAUGGUAAUCGGUUUCCUUAAUAAGUCUUGUCUUUAAGAGGUAAAUUCAAUCAGCUGCCGUCUGCUAUGAGACUGAGUGGUUGUGGCUCCGUGUGUGGGGGGUUGGUGGGGCAGGGCUGUCUUUAUUUUUCUGCUCUAUUUUCUUCUUAUUUCCCUUAGCAAUAAUUGACCCCCUUGCAUGUUAAAGACUCCCGCAAAGGUAGAAGAAGGAAGGCAUGCGCAGUGAUGCUGGAAUCAUCUUCCAUGUGGUUAUCUAAGUGUGGCCUCCAAGGAAGUUACUUCUAGAGCCCAGUUAAUUUCUGACUUAAUCAGAGCCCGGAAGCCCCAAUCAUGCUUCUGAAUUUGGUAAUGACAAGUGUCUUUGCAAACAUCUAGGAAGAAAACAAGCUUAGAGGAAGCUUUGACAGACAACAGUAGUUAAGCCCCAGCAACAGUGUGACAGAUGCCAGCUGGACAGUGUGAUAGGCUCCUGCUCAUGGGUGGACAUGGCAAGGACUGUCCAGAGGAGAAAUGGUCACCUGAGGCUGGAACACAACAAGGGCAGUCUUCCAGUAUGACUAGGCACUGAAGUUUUCAUGACUCAGCCCAUCCACCAAAGGGACUGAUCUUAAGAGUUUCAGUCUUAACCUCCCUGUGUGGUGGGACAGACACAGCAACUAAUUGGGAUGUGUGAUUCACUCACAUCGGCUCUCUACCUGGGGUCAAACCAGGCAUUCAAUUCUAACUUUGCAUUUUAAAAUGUCUGUUACAUAUCCAAUACUGCACUAGCUGUGUCAUUGCAGGAGCUCGUUUAAACUCCACAGCAGCUAUAUAAGGUGCAUAUCAGCUUCGUUUUAUUAUAUAAGGAAACCGAUGCUCAAAGAGGGGAGGUACCUAGUUCCAGACUGAGUUGAAGCUGAACCUCUGGCUUGGCAGCAGGGUAGAGAGCCCUGAGAUGUUGGCACAGAGAGUUGAGGAGUGGCCUUUAUUAUGCCGAGGCCUGCAGGUAGAUGAGCUUGAUCUUCAGUCAUCAGAUACUUACGGAAUGUCUGCAGGCACUGUGCUUGGCACUGGGGCUAAUGAUGGUUAAUGCAUUUUCUGCCCAUAGGUGAAGCCUAGUGGAAUGCUGUUUCUCAAAAUAUAUUCUUUGAUCAUGGAACUUGUCCUAGCAGGAGAUGCUCAGAAGGCAUUCAUUCAUCUCUUCAUUCAUUGUACAAAGGCUCUAAAACACUAUGUCUGGGUGGGCUCUAGGAACAUAACAGUGGGCAACACUGAUGUGAGCCUGGCCCUGGAAGCCUGCAGAGUGUCUGAUUGUGGGCGAAUACAGAUAGAACUGGGGAUAUGAUCUUUGUAAUCAUUUUAAAGGUGUGAAUAUAUGUGUAAUGCAAACAAAAUUGAAGAGGGAACGUGUACACAAUUAUUAACCAACUUUAGUGUGUUUCAUUUACAUCGUGACUGUGUGUCUUAAAAGUUUAUGUAAAAAGCAUUGCUGCAUAUUGAAGUCUCUCAAAACUGUCCAUGGCAGGUCUGGGCUCAGCAGUGCUUCUCUAGUGGCAUCCUUUAAUUUAGGCAGGCUUGUGCAACACUGUCCCAUCUUGAAGUAUUGAAGAAGACUGUAUCUCCAGGCCCUGGCUCCUCAAGCUCCCCCUGCCUACAGGAGCCUUUCAGCUGCCUUUCUCUGUGGCUCAAUGCCAUUCAUUGUUUAAGCUACGGUUCAAGGAUGAACGACUAAAGUGAUUCAUUCCUGUAUUUGACAGAUAUUUAUUGAAUGCCUACUUCAUGCCAGGCAUAGCUCUAGGCAGUAAGGAUAAGACAUAUCAGUUAAGGAAAAAAUGUAGAUACUAAAUAAUAACUUUAAUAAUGUUAAAGUAACAAUAAUAAUAUUUUAUUAUGGUAAUAACAUUAAGAAAAAAGUACUAAAGUAAUGUAUUUAUCUUAUUUAGGUAAUAAUUAUAUUAUUAUAUAUAGUAUACUAUUAUAAAUAAUAAUAAUAACUUUAAGGUAAGGUAAUAAAGGAAUAUUUAUUGCCUUCUAGUAUAUUAGAAGGUCAAAAGGUCAAUGGGAAAAAUGGAGCCGAACCAAGGAGAUUAUGGCUGUUGCAGGGAAGGCCAUUGCAGUUGAAAAGGGCGGUCAGGAUGGUUCUCAUUGAGAAAAUGACAUUUGAGCAAAAACUAUUAAAAGGUGAAGGAGUGAGCACACAUAUAUCUGGGAGAAAUGUAUUCUAGGCAAAGAGAAAGGGCAGUGGAACUGACAGAUUUGAGGACAAGCUAGGAGGCCAAUGUGAUGGACCUGAUAGAACAAAGGAAGAAGAGUAGCUGUGGAUGAGGUCGGCAAGGUCCUGGGGGUCCACCCUGAGUCUGAUGAAGGGUGCUGCUGGAGAGCGUGUUCUAGCGGAGGGUCCCAGUGGGACUCACAUUUUAGUGGCAUCACUCUGGCCACUCUAUGGCAAGAAAACAACAGGGUGUCAGGGGUGGAACUGGGGGACCCUGGCGGCAGCGUGUUCUUGAUGGACUAGUAUGGAAGGUAUGCAGGGACGCUGGAUAUAUUUUCAAGGUAAAGGCAAAAGAAUUUUCUGAAAGAUUGAAUUUGGGGCGUGAAAUAAAGAGGAGGCUCAGAUGACUCACUGUUUUUGUCCUAGCAACUAGAAGGAUGGAAUUGUCAUUAGCUGACAUGAGAAAUAAUGUGGGUAGAGCAGGAUUGGGAGGAAAGAGGAAGAGUUCUGUUUUGGGCCACGCUGAGUUUGAGUUAGGCAUUGGAGUGUAGCUUCUGAGUAGACUGCUGGUUAUUGCUGGCAAGGGAGAGGUCAAAGCUGGAAAUAUAAAUAUGGUAUUUAUCAAAAUAGAGAUGAUAUUUGAAGGUGUGAAACUAAGGCAAGAUCACCAAAGGAGUGAGUCCUGAUAAAGUAGAGAGGCUGAAGGGCCAAGUCCUGGGAAGUGCCAAUAUUAAGAAUUUAGAAAAAGAGAAAGAGGCAACCAAAGAGACUGAAAAGGAGCACACAUUGACUAGAAGGAAAAUUAAGAGACCCUGACCUCCUAGAGAUCAAGUAAAUAAAGUCUUUCUAAAAGGGAUGAUAACUCAAUUGUGUCAAUUAUUGCUAAUGGGUUUAAUAAAGAUGAAGAGAGAGUUGACCAUUGGCUUCAGCAUCGUGGAGAUCACCAUGUCCUCUGCUCUCACCCCCAGCCCACCCAGCCUGCCUCCUUUGCAUGCCAUCAUGGCAUGAUCUGCUUAUGUUGCUGCAUCUCCUGCAAAACAUUUUUCUGUCUGCCAUCCUGCAGGCACGCUCACUUGUGUGCUUAUGCAACAUUGGUGAGCACCUCCCAUGUGCUAGAUGGAAUGAGUAUGCAAAGUUAAACUUGGUAUUUUUCUACCCUCAGAUGUCUUACAGCCUAAGGAGAAAAGCAAGGUGUCUAGAAUCUGUUACAGCAAAAGAAAGGGAUUGAGGGAUAGUAAAAUUAUGAGAGUUCAGAGGACAAAGAAAUUUUCUCUGGGAGUCAAGGUUGAGUCCAUGGCUGAAGUGGCCUUUAAAUUCGGCCUUGAAUGCUGGAUAGGAUUUAGAAUUAAACAAAUGGAGGAGAAAGAAGAAUAUUUUAGAAAAAGGGGCAUAUAGGAGUAAGGGCAUGCAGGUGGGAAGGCUGGAAAGGGGACCCUGGGCUGAAGGCGUGGCAUACGGAGGAGAAGGAAGAGCGGAGAAUGAGGCUAGGAUUUGGGCCAGGGACUCAAUGAAGAGGGCCUUAGAAAAUAGAAGCUGGGCUUUAUUUCUUAGUCAGUGGAGGAAUCAUUAAAGGUUUUUGAGCCAUAGAGUGAUGCAAUAAUAGCCGUGCUGCUUUGGGAAGAGUCAUCUGGCUGUGUGUGCAGAACUGUCCAGGAGAAAGAUAAUAAGGGCCUAAAUUAGGGCAACAGAAGUGGGAGCAGAGGAGGGGGCGGAUGUGAGGCACUGUAGGAUCAGAGUUCACGGGCUCAGCACUCCAGAGGGAUAGGCACAUGGUGUGGAUCUGGGUCCCUGGGCCCUCCCUGAGAAACUCGUCAGCCUUUUGAGGUCAGUGGCCUCGGCUGUCCCUUGUGCUUGUCAUCCCCACCCCCACCCCAUCCUCUUCCAAGCCCAUGUGUGCUCAAGCUUCACCUCGUUAAUGAAAUGAAGCUGCUUAUUUUUGGAACUCUGUGAUUAACAUAGUUUCUGUGUUUAGGAAACAAAAGAACCCUGUGCAUUUCAGGACUCUCUACCUGCACUGUGUCCACCUAAAAAGCAGGGUACCACCAUCUUAAGGACAGAAAAGCUACAGGACUCUAGGAGGCCACCGUCCUGAUUUGGGAAGUCCAACUUACUUUGGCCAGACAGCAGCUAAGCUGGUUCAUCCCAUCAGCCUGGAUUGGUGAAACUGAAUCACAGGAGAUAUUUCCAGGUUUGCUGGGAUGGGAAACCUGCUCAAAGUCCUUACCAGGGAAAUUGAAAACUAUCCACACUUUUUCCUGGAUUUUGAAAAUGCUCAGCCUACAGAAGGAGAGAGAGAAAUCUGGAACCAGAUCAGCGCCGUCCUUCAGGAUUCUGAGAGCAUCCUUGCAGACCUGCAGGCUUACAAAGGCGCAGGCCCAGAGAUCCGAGAUGCAAUUCAAAAUCCCAAUGACAUUCAGCUUCAAGAAAAAGCUUGGAAUGCGGUGUGCCCUCUUGUUGUGAGGCUAAAGAGAUUUUACGAGUUUUCCAUUAGACUAGAAAAAGCUCUUCAGAGUUUAUUGGAAUCUCUGACUUGUCCACCCUACACACCAACCCAACACCUGGAAAGGGAACAGGCCCUGGCAAAGGAGUUUGCCGAAAUUUUACAUUUUACCCUUCGAUUCGAUGAGCUGAAGAUGAGGAACCCGGCUAUUCAGAAUGACUUCAGCUACUACAGAAGAACAAUCAGUCGCAACCGCAUCAACAACAUGCACCUAGACAUUGAGAAUGAAGUCAAUAAUGAGAUGGCCAAUCGAAUGUCCCUCUUCUAUGCAGAAGCCACGCCAAUGCUGAAAACCCUUAGCAAUGCCACAAUGCACUUUGUCUCUGAAAACAAAACUCUGCCAAUAGAGAACACCACAGACUGCCUCAGCACAAUGACAAGUGUCUGUAAAGUCAUGCUGGAAACUCCGGAGUACAGAAGUAGGUUUACGAGUGAAGAGACCCUGAUGUUCUGCAUGAGGGUGAUGGUGGGAGUCAUCAUCCUCUAUGACCAUGUCCACCCUGUGGGAGCUUUCUGCAAGACAUCCAAGAUCGAUAUGAAAGGCUGCAUAAAAGUUUUGAAGGAGCAGGCCCCAGACAGUGUGGAGGGGCUGCUAAAUGCCCUCAGGUUCACUACAAAGCACUUGAACGAUGAAUCAACUUCCAAACAGAUUCGAGCAAUGCUUCAGUAGAGCUCUGCUCAAAGAAGAGGAUCUAUGUGCUGACCUCAGAAGAUGUAUAUGUUUACAUAAUUUAAUACAGAUUGAUGUUAAUACUUGUGUAUUUACAUAACCGUUUCCUUCUUGUCACUGAAAUAUAUGGACCUUAAUUUGUAUCCUGACUGACUCAACCCAGCAGAGCAUAAAUUGACUUGAGAGCCUUACCUUUGAUGUCUGAAAUGAAACCCCCUUCUCCAAAGGCAAAAUUCGGAGACUUUGAUCUUUGCUACUGGAGUCCUUUAACAACAUCUAUAACGAUAAAAAAUUCCUAAUUGUUUGUGGUAGUAUUUUAAUUCUAGAUGUGUUAUCUCUCUGGGAAGUAUAGUUUAUAGAAACACAAAAUAUUUGAUUUCCUGUGUCGGCUCAGCUACAAGAAACACAACUGUUAUCUUGACAGAGGAAGAGAGGAAUCCAAGAAAAAUGCAUGUGGAGAAUUAAACCCAAGUGUUUCGAAUUCAGCACACCCCCUCUCUGUCCUCAGACUGCAGUCCACACGUGCAACUUUUCUGUUUGCACGUGUUUUAUUAAUCAGCAUACUCCUUUUCUGUUUGGAUUUAUAUCCCUCUAAUGUUCUCCUUUAAUUUCACAUGAAAAAAAAAUCUCCUGUAUUUUUUUCAGUUAGUGGGAGAGCAGCAGAAAUAGAUAGAUGUGCUGUUGCCACUGGACUGAUGAAGGUGGCUGUCUUGGAACUGGGAGACAGGUCCUCAGAGGUGCACUCAGGCAACAGGACAGCCAUCUCUCUGCUUCAGCCCUCUGCCUACAGGGAUUAGGGAAAUGGAGCUCUGGCUUUGAAGUUAUUUGUGAGUUUAGCAACCUUCCAGUUACCUGCAGAGUUCUGGGUGCACAGCCACCCCUCAUAAGAGCCCUGUUCUCUGAAGACCAUUCAUAUGAGAACAAAGGUCUAGGAUACUGCAUUAGUUACCAGAAAACUAGGGGAAUUUAGAGGGAAAAAAAAUCCAUGUUUUCUAUUUCCCAGGUUUUUAAAAAGUAGCUCUUCCCCAACCCCGUUGCUAGCUUGUUGCAAUAUAAAAGCCCUGGUGCACCUGAAUUUACUCCUGGCCUUACUAAUGAUUCAUAAUGUGAUCUUGAGAAAUGUGUUUAAGCUUUCUGAGUCUUAACCUCCUUGUCUCUAAAAUGGGCAAUUAAAACAAUCUUCAAGAGCCCUGUAAGGUUAAUGCCGAUAAAAUGACUGACUCCGCCCUUCUUCCUUAGUACGUAGUAUCCAGCAAGCAUUUGCCCCACCUUGUCUUGUUGAUGAACAAUAUUAUGAAGCCUGCAGUCAUUCUCUCUGUACAUCAGAGCUUAGUUCGAAUGGAAUCAUGAAAAUCUCUGAUUCUGACCUCCUAAGGAAAAAUGAAACCCAGAGGAUGUGGUCAUACAGGAUGGCUCCCAUGUGGGCCUAGAACCCAGGAUGCUUCACUCUUGACUCCAUGCUCUUCCUUUUAUACCAUGUGGCUGUGAAUACAUACUAUGGGAUGGGAUUCAACCCUUCUAAGUAAAUCCUCAGUCUGGUCUAUAUUGUUACUUGCCUGUUUCCACUAGAAGGAGUCACCCAGGCAUUUAGUGAAUGAUAAUCCUAGAAGUUGAGUCUGAGUACAUCAGAGUUUGGCAUUAUUUGCAACAUCCCAGGAAUGAGCUAUAAGACUCCAUUGCUUUCUGGACUUUAGUGACCAGCUGAUCUUCCCUUGGAUCCUCCAAUAAAGGGGAAAAAAUACUUGUCUUAUGUUGUUUUAGCAAGGGAGUUCAGCCAAGUGACAGGAAAGAUUCCCUGGUCUGCAUCUAAACAUUAGUCAACAGAAGGAAAAGGCUCUUUUCCUUGGAGAUUUUCAAGUUGAAAAAGUACAGCUGCUUGGAUGGAGUUUCUCUCAUCAGAAUAGAAAUAUGCUAGGUGGUCUUCAAGACCUUUUUGAACCUACAGAUUCUAAACCUUAGAGGAAGCCAGAAUAUGUGAUCAUACCAGGUGAGGAAAGUUAGGAGAUAUUCAUCUUAAGAGAUAUCCUAUUUGGCAGUCACAUGUUACACUUGAGCAACAAUUGUCUAGGCUAGAAAUAUAGAACCACACAAUAUUUAUCAUCAUUGGGUCAAUUUCUCCCCCUCUAUCAAGUGAGGAGAUUAAGGCUUAAAGAAAGGAAAGGACUUGCCAGCCACCACAGGGCUCAUGAGGGGCUUGAACCCAUGUCGUGUGUCUCUACCACAGCUGACUCUCAGCUGGCUAAUGGAGAAAAUGUGAGGAAUUACCUGUCAAAUUAGAUUGAGCUCAGAGUAAAUAGAUGAGCACAUUUAUAACUCUAAAUUAGACUUUCUAUCAAAUGGGACCAAACAUAUGGAAGGGGCUGCUGUCCUGCCUCAAUUUAGCCAAGACUUGUCUUGUCUCAAAGCCAAGACUCAGCAGUACAUGGAUUCUGAGAAGUCCAGGGUCUGAAUUGUUGUCUCUGAUUACUGGAAGGACAGGUUAACUGAAUGUCUGUGAUCACUAACAGGUGAUGGGCUUUGUGCCCACUCCAGAGAUAUUGUGGGAGACAAAUUCUUUUAACAGCCUGUCCUCCCGGCAUCAGGAGUCAUUGAACAAUCAUGGAUUGUUGUGUUUGGGAUUUUUUUUUUUUUGGCUUUGUUUUUGGUUUUUGUGUGUGUGUGUGUGUGCUGCAUGCACAUGCGUCCAAGACUUACGGGUGGUUUAGGGGAAAGUGCUAGCAACAGUGUCAAUGUCAUUGUUAACUAUAUUUCAUAUUUGAGGUCUCAUUGUUUUCAAAUAAACAGUGUUUUCCAUGACUGAGAUAUUUAUUUUUGGGAAAGCAACGAGGUAAAAAUUAUGUUUCUCAGAUGCACUGCUACUUUGGCGUUAUUACUGUGUUCUCAGAAACUCGUUGUGCACCACUAGGAAUUAGUAGUAGAAAAAAAAAAACAAUAACAAAAAAAAAAAACAACUGGAAAUGGAUGUCUUCACAUUAGGGGUGGAGUAUUAACAACCAGAAAGAAAGUUUGGAUAUUACCUUUUAACUACUAGUUAACAUCAUGCUUGAUCAACAUUUGCUCCUAGUUAUCACCAUUAAAUUAAGACCUUAAUGGUAAACUGAGGUUACUGAUGCAUCAUCACAUUUAAGUAAAAAUAAUUUCAUGUUUUCCCCAAAGAAAAAUUAAGCCUCCCAAUCUUAGGAUCCAAUUGUGCAGUAGAAUUCAGAGACUUCUCAUUCAAUCUUGUAUCCUAUGCAGCUACAAAUAUUUUUUAAAUGUUAGUAAUAAACAUUGGAAUUUUGUCUUAAAGAGUUCAAAACCUUGGAACCCAGUUUUCUCACUACGUCUAUAAAGGCCAUUACAGACCCAAGGCUGUUUUGCAGUUUUCAUAUGUUGUUUGCUGAAGUCAUUGUAAUUUUUUUUGCCUGCUUUGCCUUUUUUUCUACAGGAGUUUUGAGUGUGAAAUGAAAAUUAAAGUUUGGUACAUAUAUUUAAAAA